ACGCGGUCUGUGGGAGACCGGAGCGGGAGACAGCGGUGACAGGAGCAGCGGCCGGGAGCCCUUAGGGAGGCAGGUGAGCGGGGGCUGGAUGCGGGGAGAUAGCGGGCCUGGAGGGCGGCUCCAGGGCGAGGCGGGGACUGUGGCACCAAGAGUCCUGCGUCCCCAGAUUGUGCUGUGCGCCUGAAGCCCUGGCGGUGCAGCCGUGCACGGAGUCCCGUGGAGCGUUUGUUUGGGCUGGAUUAUCCCGCUGCAGCCGAGGUUGGGGGCCCGGGUUCGGGGCUCCGCACCUCUUCUCUGGGGUUCACCCUCUCGGAUACCGCCUGGGCAGACUCCAUCGAUGCAGAACCCGAGGUGCGGGUGGUGGUUGGUGGGGGGGUAGGGAGGUGAAAACAAUAACAGCCGUUUUGUACUAAGCGUUGCGUGCAUUGACCAUUCAUUUAUUUUAUUUAUUUAUUUAUUUUUGAGACGGAGUUUCGCUCUUGUUGCCCAGGCUGGAGUGCAAUGGCGCGAUCUCAGCUCACUGCAACCUCCGCCUCCCGGGUUCAAGCGAUUCUCCUGCCUCAGCCUGCCAACUAGCUGGGAUUACAGGCGUGUGCCACCACGCCUGCUAAUUUUUGUAUUUUUAGUAGAGAUGGGGUUUCUCCCUGUUGGUCAGGCUAGUCUCGAACUCCCGAGCUCAGGUGAUUCGCCCACCUCGGCCUCCCAAAGUGCUGGGAUUACAGGCGUGAGCCACCACGCCCGGCCUGACCCAUUCAUUUCUUACAACAACCCAUUGAGGUCGGUUCUAGUCCCCAUUUACUAAACGAAGAAACUGAGGUCACACAACUAGAAAGCUACAGAACUAGGAUUUGUACCCACAUCUAUCAGACUCCAGAGCCCACAUACUUAACCAUCCUGCUACCAACAGCAGCCAGGCCCAGAGUCUGGCUCACCCAAAGCUCUCCACAAGCCCAACCUGCUGGGAAACAGAUUUGAUAUCUAUCCUUAAAGUAUGGAGGUGUCAUGGUGGGCACUGAGGACUGGGCUGCUGGAGACCUUCCCCCAGAUCUGCCGCUGACCCACUGCGUGAUCCUGGGCCUGUGUCUACCCCUCUCUGAGCCCAGUUUCACCCUUGUUUCAGUGAUACAAUCAGCAAACUUUAAGAAGACUCUUAGCCAAGAUAUUCUAGGAUUCUGGGAAUGGCAGCUUCUCCUACGUCUAAAUGGCUAACCCCAGAGGCGAUCAGGCUCUUCAAAGCCCCAGGGCAAGGCUGGGGUCUCAUUCUUCUCUUUAAUCCCUGUGUCUAGCACUUCAGCAGGCCCAUAGUAGAUAUUCAAGAAAUGUGGGUUGGCUGAAUAAACACUUCAUCUCUUUUCAGAACUGCAUGACAGCUGCUCUCCUGGGCCUUUGUGGGGCUUUGGAUUUCUCAGUUCUGGCCACCUUCUAUCUAGCUGGCUCUCCUGACUGCCUCCUCCCUGGCCAGUGGCAGAGCCUGCCAGGGCUGGCAGCAGGUCCUAAGCCUCUGUGCGAAGACCCACAGCCUCUGGAAUCCUCAGCAUAGUACAACUUGCAGGGGUGGGGGGUGGCACAUGAAGCUCAUAGCCCCUCCUGGUAGCAGUGCUCAGGGCCCAACUUCAGUUACUCCCAGUUUGGGGAUGUUGCCUUCCAUGGGAGGAGAUACUUUCAUAUUAAAUCUGAAACACUUCUUAUCCUUCACUGUCCCCUCUUCCAUGAAACCACCCUUGACUCAGAGACACAGUCCCUCUGACAGCACCUGGUCCACCCCUCUACUCUGGCAGCCCGGUGGUGAUUAUUUUGUUUUUCCUCCACCACAUAACCUGCUGGAAGGCAGGGACUCCACUUCAGAAAUCUUGGAAAACCCUGUGGCCCACAAGGGUUUGAGCUCAUAUUCCCAUCUGGUGAGGUGCAGAAGGCACAGAGCUGUGCCAGGACAUCUCGUUCCAACCCAGCCCCACUCCUAAUAGUAAUAAAAGUAGCUACAUGUUUACUGUGCAGCUACUUGGUGCCAGACACCUACCUUAUCCCUAUCAAUAAUCUCCACAGCCUUGCAAGUUAGAGAUAUCAUGCCUAUUUUGUAGAUUAUGAAAUGAACACUGAAAGGUCAAUUACUUUGCCCAAAAUUACACAGCAGAGCAUAGACCAAACCUGGGACUGUCUGACCCUGAAACAUGGAUCUUUCUGCACCGCCCUAUACUCUGCGUCCCAGCAAAGCUAACCUGUCUGAUGUGGUUGGGCAGAGGUGCUGGACCUCCUGGCGGCUCGCUCCUGUCUUCAGUGUGGUAAUGUCACAGGCAUUUAAAUUGUGGUUUGCAAGCUCGCUUGAUUUGGGAGAAGUGCCCUCCCAGUCUGUGAAAUUCUCCCAAACUCUAAGGGCCUUUUUGCAAAGCAAAACCCACCCUGCAUUUGGCUCUGCCAAUAUGUGAUUCAGGGGGUGUUUUCCCACUCACAGAAUGGAGUGGGAAACUCCACUUAUUAAGUACCUCUUACAAUGGAAUGACUCUAUGGUGUAGGUAUCAGGGCACUGAAAUAGAAGCCAGGAGCUGCAGGGUCAGUUUAUAGCUCUGUAUGUCACUCACUGUGAUCUCCAAAAGUCCCGUUGCCUCUUUAUACCCCAUUUUCCACAUUAAAGUGUAAGGGAUUAAACAGGAUUGGCAAUUUUCAAGCUUUUAAUAUUUUCAGCACUGACAGCCGUUUCUCAAAUCAAAUCUGUCUCUGAAUCUUAAAAUUCAAAAACAGAUCAAAGUGGACUGCUGUAGUGAGACUGUUCCCUUUACUCUAACCCUGCCCCGGUCUCAGGCUCCUAGGCAGUCCUGCCCCAGGGUUUCUGCUAAGCAGGAGCCAGUUGUUCCCUCAGCCUCCUAAAAGCGAUGGGGAGUUGAGGCCAGUGGAAUGCAGCUUUGGAUUCAGAAGCCAGAAAACAACAGAGAUUGUUUGUGGGAAGUGAGUCAGAGAGAUUAGACCUCUCUUCAACAUCUGACUAGACUCUAGAAUGGCAUUAAGCAAGUCACUGAACCGCUCAGAGCCUCUGUUUCCUUAUCACUAAAAGUUAGGACAAUUCUUGCAAUGAAAUGAGAUACUACUACCAAGUACUUCAGUGCUGUGCCCAGCACAGAACGAAUACACUCAGUAUGUUUUUCUUUUGUUUCUUCUGUCUCUCCAGCACCCAAAGCAGAAACAGUAUGGGCAGAGAGACGCCUACUGAAUCAGUUGUUCCCUCAGCCUCCUGAAAGCAAUGAGGAGUUGAGGCCACGGGAAUGCAGCUUUGGAUUCCAGAAGCCAAGGACCUGUUACAAAGGUGGUUUUCUGGGAAGCAAAUUAGAGGGAUUAGACCUGGCUUCGACAUCUGACUUGACUCCAACCUACCAAAGGAUCUCCCAGUUCACCUGGGAGUUAACACACCAGGGUUCUAGUCCUUUUGCUCGCUGUGUGGCUUUGGGCUGAACCCACUCAUCCUGCAAAACCAAGUUCAACGCCCUGUCAUUUUCUUUUUUUUUUUUUUUUUUGAGAUGGAGUCUCACACUGUCGCCCAGGCUAGAGUGCAAUGGGUGCACUCUCGGCUCACUGCAACCUCUGCCUCCUAGGUUCAAUCGAUUCUUCUGCCUCAGCCUCCAGAGGAACUCUGACUACAGGUGCACACCACCACACCCAGCUAAUUUUUGUAUUUUUAUUUUUAUUUCUAUUUAUUUAUUUAUUGUGAGAUGGAGUUUCUCUCUUGUUGCCCAUGCUGGAGUGCAAUGGCACGAUCUCGGCUCAUUGCAACCUCCGCCUCCCAAGUUCAAAGGAUUCUCCUAUCUCAGCUUCUGAAGUAGCUGGGAUUACAGGCAUGUGCCACCACACCCGGCUAAUUUUUUUUUAUUUUUAGUAGAGAUGGGGUUUCACCAUGUUGGUCAGGCUGGUCUCAAACUCCUGACCUCAAGUGAUCCACCCACCUCGGCCUCCCAAAGUGCUGGGAUUACAGGCGUGAGCCACCGUGCCUGGCCUAAUUUUUGUAUUUUUAGUAGAGACGGAGUUUCACCACAUUGGCCAGCCUGGUCUCAAACUCCAGACCUCAAGUGAUCCACCCGCCUCAGCCUCCCAAAGUGCUGGGGUUACAGGUGUGAGCCACUACGCCUGGCGCCUGUCUUCUUCUAAUAUGCCUCUUCUGACCUCCUCACUCCCAUUGGAGCCAUGGCUCACUUCUGGUCAGGCUCCAUGCACUCAAUCAGCCCUGCCUGCCAGGACUGUAGUGCCCACUUGAUGAGAAAUCACCUGUGAAAAUGCCAGGCAUGGUCUGGCACACAGUAGGUGCUCAAGAAACAAAUGUUAAUGCCCCAGCUUCCUUCUGUCUUGUGUCCACUAAUUUGGCAUUUGGAGCAUAUUUUUGUACUUCACGUAAUUAAAUAUUUACUGUGUGCCAAGGUCAGUGUGUGACAGAGCACUGUAGGGGAGGCAAAAAUGAACCAACUCUGGACCUUGCCCUGCAGAAGCUCUGUCUACUGGCAUGAGACAGAGCCUGCAGCCAAUGCCCCAGGAGCCCUCGGUUCCAACCAACUGAUGCCCCUGUGCCCACUGGCCCACGCCAUGCAGCCCCAGUCCGUUCUGCACAGCGGCUACUUCCACCCACUACUUCGGGCCUGGCAGACAGCCACCACCACCCUCAAUGCCUCCAACCUCAUCUACCCCAUCUUUGUCACGGAUGUUCCUGAUGACAUACAGCCUAUCACCAGCCUCCCAGGAGUGGCCAGGUAUGGUGUGAAGCGGCUGGAAGAGAUGCUGAGGCCCUUGGUGGAAGAGGGCCUACGCUGUGUCUUGAUCUUUGGCGUCCCCAGCAGAGUUCCCAAGGACGAGCGGGGUUCCGCAGCUGACUCCGAGGAGUCCCCAGCUAUUGAGGCAAUCCAUCUGUUGAGGAAGACCUUCCCCAACCUCCUGGUGGCCUGUGAUGUCUGCCUGUGUCCCUACACCUCCCAUGGUCACUGCGGGCUCCUGAGUGAAAACGGAGCAUUCCGGGCUGAGGAGAGCCGCCAGCGGCUGGCUGAGGUGGCAUUGGCGUAUGCCAAGGCAGGAUGUCAGGUGGUAGCCCCGUCGGACAUGAUGGAUGGACGCGUGGAAGCCAUCAAAGAGGCCCUGAUGGCACAUGGACUUGGCAACAGGGUAUCGGUGAUGAGCUACAGUGCCAAAUUUGCUUCCUGUUUCUAUGGCCCUUUCCGGGAUGCAGCUAAGUCAAGCCCAGCUUUUGGGGACCGCCGCUGCUACCAGCUGCCCCCUGGAGCACGAGGCCUGGCUCUCCGAGCUGUGGACCGGGAUGUACGGGAAGGAGCUGACAUGCUCAUGGUGAAGCCGGGAAUGCCCUACCUGGACAUCGUGCGGGAGGUAAAGGACAAGCACCCUGACCUCCCUCUCGCCGUGUACCACGUCUCUGGAGAGUUUGCCAUGCUGUGGCAUGGAGCCCAGGCCGGGGCAUUUGAUCUCAAGGCUGCCGUACUGGAGGCCAUGACUGCCUUCCGCAGAGCAGGUGCUGACAUCAUCAUCACCUACUACACACCGCAGCUGCUGCAGUGGCUGAAGGAGGAAUGAUGGAGACAGUGCCAGGCCCAAGAACUAGAACUUUAAAACGUUCCCGGGGCCUCAGACAAGUGAAAACCAAAGUAAAUGCUGCUUUUAGAACUGUGCCCUCAUGCCCUCUUCCUGCUCACAUGCUAGCGGGGCCCAGCAGCCCUGGGUGGUUUUGCCAGCAUGCUAACUCUUGUAACUCGCAGCUGCAUCCUAUGAGCUCUCCCAAGCUUCCCCGCCCCUCCCCUGGGUCAGCCGUGAGGCCCACCUUUGCCACCCUCAGCUCUUUCCUCUGGUGUGGCUUCAGCUUGAAAGCAACCUGGAGUCGGGGGCACAGCCUUUGGGGCCUGGCUGGGAGAGGGUCUUGGAGCAUUAGGGGAAGAAGAGAGCAGUGGGAUCUUGGGGCCUGAGAAGCCUUGGAACGCUUCUGGCAGCAGAGCUGGGUGUGGGAAUGAGGCCUAGAUCGAUAUCCCUGGGUUAGAGUUGAAAUUUGCCGCAAUUCCACUGGAAGGCAUUUCCCACGAGGCCAGAGGUUGCCAGGCUGCCUGAGGUCUCCUAUUCUACUCUGAACCAUAAACCCAGAGAAGAAUUACUCAUUAACCAGCAUAAAUACUGCCUGAGGAUCAAAACUCAGAGGCAAAGAGGGAGUUCCUGACUGCUAGAGGUGCCACCACCACAAACACUUUUUAUUCAGGAGAUACUUUUUGAGAAUCUCUGCUCUGUUCCUAGGUUCAGUGCUGGGUCCUGGGAAUACAGCAGGACAGACCUCAGCUUAUCUCUUCAUAGAAAUUAUACAAAGAGAAUUGGGGAGACAGCUAAGAAGAAAACAAAGAAAUAAAGCAGUUACAAAUUGUGAUAAGUGCUUUGAAGGAAAGAAGGGGUCUGAGACAACAACAGGGAAGGGGCCUCUCUUGAAACAGUAGUUGGGAAGGAGGCAGACAUGCACCAGUGAUGUGGUGACAGGUGCUCUGAAGGAGGUCACCAGGACCUGACCUCUUUGAAGGAUCAGAAAAUACUUCCCUGAAGGACUGACAUUUGAGCCUAGACCUGAAGGGUGAGCCAUCAAGCUAAGACAAUUGGGGAAGAGCAUUCCAGGGAGAGGGAGGAGUUGUGCAAAGGCCCUGGGGCUCCUUCUAGCUGGAGGAAUGCAAGGCUAGCUUGUCUGGAGCACUGAGAGGAUGGCCUGAACUGAGUGGAGAGAGACAGACCAGGACCAAACCAUGCAGAGGUCAAGGGCCACAUUCACCUUUUCAGAGUGACUCAAUCAAAUUUGUAGUUUGUAAAAGUAUUUUAACAGCUCUGCGGCAAAGUGCAAAUGAAAAGUCUUGAUGGCAUGGACUGGAGCGGGGACAGUGGGGAUGGAGAAAGGGGAAUGGAUUGUGGAUGUGUUUAGAAGGUAGAUUCGAUGUGAAGGAUGAAUCUGGCUUGACCUUCUGGGUGGCUGAUGGGCCAUUUACUGAGAUGGGGCAGCCUGGAAGAGGAACAGAAGCAGGGUCGGGGUGGAGGGAGAAUACUAAACUUAGCUUGAGACAUUUUGCAAUAAGGAAGCUAUAUCUAGAGUGCUUAUGUGACUCACCUAAGGCCACUCAACAAGUUUGUGGCAGAACUGGAUUAGAACUGCACAGAAAACAGCCAAGCUGGGAUUUGAACCCAUGUAGUCCAACUCCAAGGCCUCUGCCCCUAACCACUGUGCCAUACCACCUCCCAAUAAUCAACAGCAAAAUUAUAGGUCUAACAAUGUUUUAUAGACACCCCUCCAUUUAUGUGAUGGGUUUGCAUCCUGAUAAACCCAUCAUAAGUUGAAAAUAUGAUCAUAAGUUGAAAAUAUGAUCAUAAGUCAAAAAUGUAUUUAAUAUACCUAACCUACCAAACAUCAUAGCUUAGCCUAGCCUGCCUUAAACAUGCUCAGAACACUUACAUUAGCCUACAGUGGGCAAAACUAUCCAACACAAAAUCUAUAUUGUAAUAAAGUUGUAAAGAAUUUUGAAUAAAAAUUCAAUAUUUGAAGUACA